GUGACUGGGCUGUGCCAGUCUGGGGAUGAUCCCACAGCUGAGCUCCUGUAGAUGGAACCAGAGGUGAGGCAAGGAACUGGAGGCCCUCCCCACUGAGGUCAGCGGGGCGCAGACGCCCCCUUGUCGUGCCCUGCCUUCCUCCUGCAAUCCUGCAGGACUCUCCAGGGCCAAGUGCUGCCCUUGGGGCCAAAAAACAGGGCCUUCUCCUUCACCUGCCCUGCAGCCAUUCAGGUGCGAGGAAGUGGCUGGAGUGGAGGAAGGAGGUUGAGCUGCUCUCAGAUGUGGCCUACUUUGGCCUCACCACACUUGCAGGCUACCAGACCCUGGGGGAGGAGUACGUCAGCAUCAUCCAGGUGGACCCAUCGCGGAUACAUGUGCCCUCCUCGCUGCGCCGUGGCGUGCUGGUGACACUGCAUGCCGUCCUGCCCUACCUGCUGGACAAGGCCCUGCUCCCCCUGGAGCAGGAGCUGCAGGCUGACCCCGACAGUGGGCGACCCUUGCAGGGGAGCCUGGGGCCAGGUGGGCGUGGCUGCUCAGGGGCGCGGCGCUGGAUGCGUCACCACACGGCCACCCUGACUGAGCAGCAGAGGAGGGCGCUGCUGCGGGCGGUCUUCGUCCUCAGACAGGGCCUCGCCUGCCUCCAGCGGCUACAUGUUGCCUGGUUUUACAUCCACGGUGUCUUCUACCACCUGGCCAAGAGGCUCACGGGGAUCACGUACGCGCUGAGGCCAGAUCCCCUCAGGGUCCUGAUGAGUGUGGCGCCAUCUGCCUUACAGCUCCGUGUCCGCAGCCUGCCCGGAGAGGACCUGAGGGCCCGUGUUAGCUACAGGCUGCUGGGGGUCAUCUCACUGCUGCACCUGGUGCUGUCCAUGGGGCUGCAGCUGUACGGUUUCAGGCAGCGGCAGCGAGCCAGGAAGGAGUGGAGGCUGCACCGCGGCCUGUCUCACCGCAGGGCCUCCUUGGAGGAGAGAGCCGUUUCCAGAAACCCCCUGUGCACCCUGUGCCUGGAGGAGCGCAGGCACCCAACAGCCACGCCCUGCGGCCACCUGUUCUGCUGGGAGUGCAUCACCGCGUGGUGCAGCAGCAAGGCGGAGUGUCCCCUCUGCCGGGAGAAGUUCCCUCCCCAGAAGCUCAUCUACCUUCGGCACUACCGCUGAGCCGGCGCCCGGGUGGGCCUGGACACAGAUGACCUCUACGGGAGUCUGAACGCCAAGAUUUAGUCUCAGGAUUAACCUUGCUUGCACAGAAGUUAGAACACUCUCAGUUUUUUGUCAUGUAAGAUACUAACCUAGCCACCCUGGGAGAGAACAGAAAGCUGUCCCUGGCUGCGCUUUCUCAGCCCUGGGAGGGGCGCCUGAACCCAGAACAUUUCCCUAACCCCAACCUGGUAGGACUCAGCCACUUCUUCAGGAAUUUCACUUAUUUGGACGGGAUUUUAGGUUUCCCUCCCUUCCCCAAACCAUACAGUUGAGAAGUAAUUCAGAAGUAGGCCAGAAGACACUUUAUUCGUUUAUAUUGUGAGAAAACAGCCCCAUCAGGCUUGUGUUAAGGCAAUGGACUGAAUGAGUGCGUGCUGGGUGGGGUGGGGCACGGAGGCUGGCGGGUUGCUUCAGCCAGUGCAGUGAGAACAGCAGCCCCACGGCCCCAUGGGAGGCGGCGCUGCUCUCCCCGAGGGCGGCUGGGCAGAGCACAUCCCCCAGGACUUGAUGACCACACGGGGCAGAGAGAAACCAACCAAGGCCAGCACCUCCGUCGGAAGCAUUUGGCACACACACCUUCAAUACACGUCAAGGUCGCUUCCAGUUUUAGAAAACAGAAAUCUGCAUCUCAGCCUGAGACGCACAGAGAGGUCUCUUCCUGACCCAGACGCACUCACGAGCCAGGUCCUGGGGGUAUGGGGGCUGCCAGGGGCGCCCGAGCCCUCUCCUGGGGGGCCUGCUGGGCAGGCGACCUGCUGACCCACGGUCACUGCUGUGUUCAGCCCCUCAGCUCGGCCCCAGCCUAUUUCCCGCCUCCAUUUGAUGUUUCCAGGUUUUCAAAACUGCAUUUAACCUGCGCCAGAGAGUUCACCGUAGGCAUCUUUAAUAAACUAACUCCAGCAAAAUGUGGGUACGUUACUAACACAAGAUGGAACUUGAGAUUUCCUGAAGCGCAGUGUUAAAAUGCCUCGAGGGCGUGUGCCACAUUUCCCUGCUGACGUAAAACACCUGGCCAGCAGGACCGGCUUCCGGCAAAGACCCGCGCAAACCAUGUCUUGCUGUUUGACUUACUUAGGAAUGAGGAUGACCCUGUAUUCCUGGGUUAGUCAAGGUCAGCUUGCCAGAGACGGAGGAGGGCGGGGGGGCCGUGACCCUCUAGACUGGGAGGACCACCAGGAGAGGCACUGGGGGCUGCGGCCGGGUGGGCAGAUGCCGCCGUGGCUCCAUCCAUCAGCACCCAGUCCUUUGCUUCACUGUGCUCUGGCCAAGCGCGUGCGACUUCCUGUCACACCUUAGGCCUGAGCGCUUAUUAAGAAAACAGUAUGAAAAAUGACAAACACUCCUGUCCACAGUCUGAGAAUCCCAAGUGUCUCAACACGGUACCAGAAGUACCACCUGGGAGCAGCACUGGCUAUCUUGGGUCAGGGACACACAAGCUUGAACGUGGCCUCUUAGAGGAGCUCGAUGUCAGAUAUGUAAACACUGGUACAAGAAAAUCCAGACACUAAGCAUUCACCGUGUCAAUUCUGAGACAGGAAACACCGCCCAGAGUGAGGAGCCUGCGCAGCCCGGGGCCCAGGAGGAGAGGCCUUCACUCGCAUGUCAGUGUCUCAUCUGGGACCACAGCUGUGAUGUUCUGCUGUGCAAUAUGGGUCACCUUUCGAAAAGGCCAAACAAAAGGUGGGCUUUCCUGUGUCCAGCGACUGCCAUGUUUUAGGUAAAGACUUUAGUAAAGGUGGAGGUAAAAUCA